AGAGGAGCCGCCGAGCCCAGCACAGCUGCCCUCUGGACCCUGCGGACCCCAGCCGAGCCCCUUCCUGAGUUCCACAGGCGCAGCCCCCGGGCGGUCGGGCGGAGGGGUCCCCGGGGCGGUGCCAGGGCGCAAUCCUGGAGGGCGGCCGGGAGGAGGAGGUGCGCGCGGCCAUGCACACCGUGGCUACGUCCGGACCCAACGCGUCCUGGGGGGCACCGGCCAACGCCUCCGGCUGCCCGGGCUGUGGCGCCAACGCCUCGGACGGCCCAGUCCCUUCGCCGCGGGCCGUGGACGCCUGGCUCGUGCCGCUCUUCUUCGCGGCGCUGAUGCUGCUGGGCCUGGUGGGGAACUCGCUGGUCAUCUACGUCAUCUGCCGCCACAAGCCGAUGCGGACCGUGACCAACUUCUACAUCGCCAACCUGGCGGCCACGGACGUGACCUUCCUCCUGUGCUGCGUCCCCUUCACGGCCCUGCUGUACCCGCUGCCCGGCUGGGUGCUGGGCGACUUCAUGUGCAAGUUCGUCAACUACAUCCAGCAGGUCUCGGUGCAGGCCACGUGUGCCACUCUGACCGCCAUGAGUGUGGACCGCUGGUACGUGACGGUGUUCCCGUUGCGCGCCCUGCACCGCCGCACGCCCCGCCUGGCGCUGGCUGUCAGCCUCAGCAUCUGGGUAGGCUCUGCGGCGGUGUCUGCGCCGGUGCUCGCCCUGCACCGCCUGUCACCCGGGCCGCGCGCCUACUGCAGUGAGGCCUUCCCCAGCCGCGCCCUGGAGCGCGCCUUCGCACUGUACAACCUGCUGGCGCUGUACCUGCUGCCGCUGCUCGCCACCUGCGCCUGCUAUGCGGCCAUGCUGCGCCACCUGGGCCGGGUCGCCGUGCGCCCCGCGCCCGCCGAUAGCGCCCUGCAGGUGCGCGGCGUGGGUGGGAGGACAGCAAGGCUGGGCGGGCGGGGAGGCACCGUGGUGGGAGGCGCCGGUGGGGGCAUCUGCGCGGGCAGGGACAGCCCAAGGGGUCCAGGAGGGGCGGUGCGAGGGGAUGAGCUGAGCCGGGCCCCAGCCUUUCGUCUAACCACCUUCACGGCACCCCCCCAGGGGCAGGUGCUGGCAGAGCGCGCAGGCGCCGUGCGGGCCAAGGUCUCGCGGCUGGUGGCGGCCGUGGUCCUGCUCUUCGCCGCCUGCUGGGGCCCCAUCCAGCUGUUCCUGGUGCUGCAGGCGCUGGGCCCCGCGGGCUCCUGGCACCCACGCAGCUACGCCGCCUACGCGCUUAAGACCUGGGCUCACUGCAUGUCCUACAGCAACUCCGCGCUGAACCCGCUGCUCUACGCCUUCCUGGGCUCGCACUUCCGACAGGCCUUCCGCCGCGUCUGCCCCUGCGCGCCGCGCCGCCCCCGCCGCCCCCGCCGGCCCGGACCCUCGGACCCCGCAGCCCCACACGCGGAGCUGCUCCGCCUGGGGUCCCACCCGGCCCCCGCCAGGGCGCAGAAGCCAGGGAGCAGUGGGCUGGCCGCGCGCGGGCUGUGCGUCCUGGGGGAGGACAACGCCCCUCUCUGAGCGGACCCGGUGGGAAUCCGAGCGGCUCCCUCGGGAGCGGGGACUGCUGGAACAGCGGCUAUUCUUCUGUUAUUAGUAUUUUUCUUACUGUCCAAGAUCAACUGUGGAAAUAUUUUGGUCUCUUGUGACGUUCGGUGCAGUUUCGUUGUGAAGUUUGCUAUUGAUAUUGAAAUUAUGACUUCUGUGUUUCCUGAAAUUAAACAUGUGUCAACACAGGACUUUCUGGAUCAUUCCAGAAAGUGUCAGACGUUUUCUCA